CCUGCGCGCGCAGCUGGUCGGCCCGCGGCGGUGCUGCGCGGAUCCGGCGUCGGGGCCCGGCAUGGCGGGGGCCGGGGCCAAGCCGGGCCGGACCCGGACCUAAAUGCCUCUGUUCUUCUCCGCGCUGUUGGUCUUGCUGCUAGUUGCGCUUAGCGCCCUCUUUCUAGGCCGGUGGCUUGUGGUCCGGUUGGCCACCAAGUGGUGUCAGCGGAAGCUGCAGGCGGAGCUAAAGAUUGGCUCCUUCCGCUUUUUUUGGAUCCAGAAUGUCAGUCUUAAGUUUCAGCAACACCAGCAAACAGUGGAAAUUGAUAACCUGUGGAUUUCCAGCAAACUCCUUAGCCAUGAUCUUCCACACUAUGUGGCAUUGUGCUUUGGAGAAGUGCGUAUCAGAACGGACCUACAGAAAGUUUCUGACCUGUCUGCCCCAUUCUCCCAGAGCGCUGGGGUGGAUCAAAAGGAACUGUCCUUCAGCCCAUCCUUAUUGAAGAUCUUCUGCCAAGUGAGACAACUUCUCCUGCUAUCCUGGACUGUACUUUGGCAUGGUUGGCUUUGGAGUUAUGGCUAUUCUCCAUUCAUGUAGAUGCUAUAAACAUCAUGGUUCUCAAGGUGGAUACCUCUGAGUCCUUAUGGCAUAUUCAGAUCAGUAGAAGCAGAUUUCUUUUGGAUAGUGAUGGGAAAAGGCUAAUCUGUGAGGUGAGCUUAUGUAAGAUCAACAGCAAAGUUCUAAAGAGUGGUCAGCUGGAGGACACCUGCCUAGUGGAGCUUUCACUGGCCCUGGACCUGUGUCUAAAGGUGGGCAUUAGCAGUCGGCAUCUCACUGCUAUCACUGUGGAUGUGUGGACACUCCAUGCUGAACUGCAUGAGGGCCUCUUCCAGAGCCAACUGCUGUGCCAGGGCCCAAGCCUAGCAUCUAAGCCUGUUCCCUGUUCAGAGGUGACAGAAAACUUAGUUGAGCCAACUCUGCCUGGCCUAUUCCUUCUCCAGCAGCUGCCAGACCAGGUCAAGGUUAAGAUGGAGAACACAAGCGUGGUAUUGUCCAUGAAUAGUCAAAAGAGGCACCUGACUUGGACUCUGAAGCUGCUGCAGUUCCUGUACCACCGUGAUGAGGAUCAGCUGCCCCUUCGAAGCUUCACAGCAAACUCUGAUAUGGCACAGAUGAGCACUGAACUGCUGCUGGAAGAUGGGUUGUUGUUGUCCCAGAGUCGCCAACGCAUUGUCUGCCUCAACUCCCUCAAGGCUAGUGUGCAGGUGACCACCAUUGACCUCUCAGCCUCCCUAGUUCUGAACACUUGCAUCAUUCACUACCGGCACCAGGAAUUCUCUCACUGGCUGCACCUGCUAGCACUGGAAACCCAAGGGUCUAGUUCACCUGUUCUAAAGCAAAGGAAAAAAAGAACCUUCCCCCAAAUCCUGGCUCCCAUCAUCUUUAGCACCUCCAUCUCCAAUGUCAACAUUUCCAUUCAACUUGGAGAUACACCACCUUUUGCCUUGGGAUUCAAUUCUAUCUCUCUGGAUUACCAGCACCUCAGGCCACAAAGCAUCCAUCAGCGGGGCGUCCUAACUGUGGACCACCUCUGCUGGCGUGUGGGCAGUGACUCCCACAUUCAGCGGGCGCCACACCCACCCAAUAUGCAUGUUUGGGGUGAGGCACUUGUUCUGGACUCCUUCACACUACAGGGUAGCUAUAACCAGCCUCUGGGCCUGUCCAGCACCCAGUCAGAUACCCUUUUUCUUGAUUGUACCAUUCGAGGACUUCAGGUGGAAGCAUCAGAUACCUGUGCCCAAUGUCUGUCUCGUAUCUUAUCCCUGAUGGGUCCACAAUCUGGGAAGUCAGCUGUCUCUAGGCACUCUUCAUUUGGGGAAUCUGUGUCAUUACUGUGGAAGGUGGACUUGAAGGUCGAAGACAUGAACUUGUUUACCCUUUCUGCCUUGGUUGGUGCUUCAGAGGUACGACUGGACACCCUAACUAUCCUGGGCAGUGCAGAGACGUCCACUGUGGGGAUUCAAGGACUUGUGUUAGCGCUGGUGAAAUCAGUCACGGAGAAGAUGCAACCCUGUUGCAAGGCCCCUGACAUCCCUACCCCAGUGCUCAGCCUUUCCAUGCUCUCCAUCACCUAUCACAGCAGCAUCCGCUCUCUGGAGCUCGUAUGUUUUUAACUUUUUGUGGAAUUUAAAAUACAUACAAAACUAGAGAGAAUUUAUAAGCUUUUGUAUACCAAGAUUCAAUAAUUACCAAUUCAUGACCAACUUCUUUUAAUUAUACUGUCACCAAUUUCCCCUGCCUCAGGCUCUGGGAUUAUUUUGAAGUAGGUUCAGUGUGGUGCAGGGCUGACCUUACUUUGGAGCCCCCCAGAUCACAUGUACCUGUACCAGCAUGUCCUGGCCACUCUACAGUGCCGAGACCUACUAAGAGCCACUGUGUUUCCUGAGACUGUACCAUCCCUUGCACUAGAGACUUCAGGAACUACUUCUGAGCUAGAAGGCCGUGCCCCUGAGCCAUUACCCCCAAAGCGGCUGCUAAACCUAACCCUGGAGGUGAGCACAGCCAAGCUCACAGCUUUUGUAGCUGAGGACAAGUUCAUUACCCUGGCUGCAGAGAGUGUGUCACUGAGCCGGCAUGGAGGUUCCCUGCAGGCAUACUGUCCAGAGCUGGCUGCUGGCUUUGAUGGCAAUAGUAUCUUCAACUUCAAGGAGGUGGAGGUGCAGCUGCUACCUGAGCUGGAAGAGAUGAUCCUCCACCGGAACCCCUUCCCUGCGCUGCAGACCCUCCGGAACCGUGUUUGGCUCCUCUCUUUCGGCUCAGUCUCGGUGGAGUUUCCUUAUCAGUAUGACUUUUCUCGAACUCUAGAUGAGGCUGUGGGAGUUCAGAAGUGGCUGAAGGGACUACAUCAAGGGACUCGUGCUUGGGCCUCUCCAAGCCCUGUCCCACUCCCACCUGAUCUACUCUUAAAGGUUGAGCACUUCUCAUGGGUUUUCUUGGAUGAUGUUUUUGAGGUGAAACUUCAUGAUAACUACGAGCUGAUGAAGGAUGAAAGUAAGGAGAGUGCCAAAAGACUACAGCUACUGGAUGCUAAAGUGGCCGCCCUUCGGAAGCAGCAUGGGGAGUUGUUGCCUGCCCGCAAAAUUGAGGAGCUCUAUGCCUCUUUGGAACGCAAAAACAUUGAAAUCUACAUCCAGCGUUCCCGUCGUCUCUAUGGCAACACACCCAUGCGCCGGGCACUGCUUACUUGGAGCUUAGCAGGGCUAGAACUGGUAGCUCUGGCAGAUGCCUCCUUCCAUGGUCCUGAGCAUGUGGUAGAACAGGUUCAAGAGCUUGAUCCAGGCAGCCCUUUUCCCCCUGAGGGAUUAGAUCUUGUCAUUCAGUGGUGUCGAAUGCUCAAGUGCAAUGUCAAGAGCUUUCUGGUUCGGAUCAGGGACUAUCCACGGUACCUGUUUGAGAUCCGUGACUGGCGGCUAAUGGGUCGACUUGUGGGCACCGAGCAGAGUGGUCAGCCUUGCUCCCGUCGGCGUCAGAUCUUGCACUUGGGGCUUCCGUGGGGUAACGUGGCAGUGGAGAGGAACAUGCCCCCACUCAAAUUCUACCAUGACUUUCACUCGGAAAUAUUCCAGUACACAGUGGUGUGGGGCCCAUGCUGGGAUCCAGCCUGGACACUAAUUGGCCAGUGUGUGGACCUCUUGACCAAGCCCUCAGCUGACCCCAGCCCACCUUUGCCCUGGUGGGACAAGAGCCGUCUUCUGUUCCAUGGAGACUGGCACAUGGACAUUGAACAGGCGAACCUGCACCAGCUGGCCACUGAGGAUCCAUACAACACAACUGAAAAUAUGCACUGGGAGUGGAGCCACCUGUCUUUUCAUUGGAAACCUGGUCAGUUUGUGUUCAAGGGUGACUUGGAUAUCAACGUGAGAACAGCCUCUAAGUAUGACGACUGCUGCUUCCUUCACCUGCCUGACCUCUGCAUGACACUGGACCUGCAGUGGCUGUGCCAUGGGAACCCCCAUGAUCACCAUAGUGUCACUCUGCGGGCCCCAGAGUUCCUGCCUGAGGUGCCCUUGGGCCAGCUUCAUGACUCCUACCGGGCCUUUCGCUCGGAGAACCUCAAUCUCUCCAUCAAGAUGGAUCUGACUCGGCACAGUGGAACAAUAUCCCAGCCCCGAAUUCUGCUAUAUAGUAGUACCCUGCGCUGGAUGCAAAACUUCUGGGCAACUUGGACAAGUGUCACAAGGCCUAUCUGCAGGGGAAAGCUCUUCAAUAACCUGAAACCCAGCAAGAAGAAACUUGGUCAGCACUACAAGCAACUUUCCUAUACAGCCCUCUUUCCCCAGCUGCAGGUACAUUAUUGGGCCUCAUUUGCCCAGCAACGGGGCAUCCAGAUUGAGUGCAGUCAGGGCCAUGUCUUCACUCGGGGGACUCAGCGGCUUAUACCUCAAGGCACAGUGAUGCGGCGCCUUAUCUCUGAUUGGAGUGUUACCCAGAUGGUGAGUGACCUAAGUCAGGUGACCGUUCACCUGAUGGCCUCACCCACUGAAGAGAAUGCUGAUCACUGUCUUGAUCCCUUGGUAACAAAGACCCACCUGCUGAGCUUGUCCUCCCUCACCUACCAACGGCAUAGCAAUCGCACAGCUGAGGAGGAGCUCUCUGCUCGUGAUGGGGAUCCUACCUUUCAUACACAUCAGCUGCACUUAGUAGAUUUACGGAUUUCCUGGACAACUACCAAUCGAGACAUUGCCUUUGGGUUAUAUGAUGGGUACAAAAAGGCAGCUGUACUCAAACGUAAUCUUUCUACUGAGGCCCUGAAGGGGUUAAAGAUUGAUCCACAGAUGCCAGCCAAAAAGCCAAAGCGGGGUGUCCCAACUAGUGCCUCAGCCCCACCUCGUGUUAACACUCCCAGCUUCAGUGGACAACCUGAUAAGGGGUCAUCAGGAGGUGCUUACAUGUUGCAGAAGCUAAUUGAAGAGACAGAUAGGUUUGUAGUGUUCACAGAAGAGGAAUCAGGCAUGAGUGACCAGUUGUGUGGCAUUGCUGCCUGCCAGACGGAUGACAUAUACAACCGAAACUGCCUUAUUGAAUUGGUCAACUGUCAGAUGGUUCUUCGUGGAGCAGAGACAGAAGGCUGUGUCAUUGUGUCAGCUGCCAAAGCCCAACUGCUGCAGUGCCAGCACCAUCCAGCCUGGUAUGGUGAUACAUUGAAGCAAAAGACAUCCUGGACUUGCCUCUUGGAUGGCAUGCAGUACUUUGCCACCACUGAAAGCAGCCCCACAGAGCAGGAUGGCCGACAGCUCUGGUUAGAGGUGAAGAAUAUCGAGGAGCACCGGCAGCGUAGUCUGGACUCUGUGCAGGAGCUGAUGGAGAGUGGGCAGGCAGUGGGCGGCAUGGUUACCACAACCACAGAUUGGAACCAGCCAGCUGAGGCACAGCAAGCCCAGCAAGUCCAGCGGAUCAUUUCGCGUUGCAACUGCCGAAUGUACUAUAUUAGUUACAGCCAUGACAUUGAUCCUGAACUAGCAACUCAGAUUAAGCCACCUGAAGUUCUUGAGAACCAGGAAAAGGAAGAUCUCCUAAAGAAGCAGGAAGGGGCUGUGGAUACCUUCACCCUUAUCCACCAUGAGCUGGAAAUUUCCACCAACCCAGCUCAGUAUGCCAUGAUCCUGGACAUUGUCAACAACCUGCUGCUCCAUGUAGAACCUAAGCGGAAGGAACAUAGUGAGAAGAAGCAACGGGUCAGGUUCCAGCUUGAGAUCUCUAGCAAUCCAGAGGAGCAACGCAGCAGCAUACUGCAUUUGCAGGAGGCUGUGCGGCAGCAUGUGGCCCAAAUACGACAGCUGGAGAAGCAGAUGUAUUCUAUCAUGAAGUCUUUGCAGGAUGACAGCAAGAAUGAGAAUCUGCUUGACCUGAACCAGAAGCUUCAGUUGCAGCUAAACCAGGAGAAGGCCAACCUGCAGCUGGAAAGUGAAGAACUGAAUAUCCUCAUCAGGUGUUUUAAGGAUUUCCAACUGCAGCGGGCUAACAAGAUGGAGCUGCGAAAGCAGCAAGAAGAUGUGAGUGUGGUCCGUCGCACUGAGUUUUACUUUGCUCAGGCACGGUGGCGCCUGACAGAGGAAGAUGGACAGCUGGGAAUUGCUGAAUUAGAACUGCAGAGGUUCCUCUACAGCAAGGUGAAUAAGUCUGAUGACACAGCAGAACAUCUUCUGGAGUUGGGCUGGUUUACCAUGAACAACCUCCUCCCCAAUGCUGUCUAUAAGGUAGUACUGCGGCCCCAGAGCUCCUGCCAGUCUGGGCGACAGCUAGCUCUCCGCCUCUUCAGCAAAGUUCGGCCCCCUGUUGGGGGUAUCUCUGUUAAGGAGCAUUUUGAGGUAAAUGUGGUGCCUCUCACCAUCCAGCUGACACACCAGUUCUUCCACAGAAUGAUGGGCUUUUUCUUUCCUGGCCGAAGUGUGGAAGAUGAUGAAGUUGGUGAUGAAGAGGAUAAGUCCAAACUGGUGACUACUGGAAUACCAGUGGUGAAGCCUCGGCAGCUGAUUGCAACAGAUGAUGCAGUACCACUGGGCCCUGGGAAGGGUGUGGCACAGGGUUUGACUCGGAGUUCUGGGGUCAGAAGGUCAUUUCGCAAAUCGCCAGAGCACCCUGUGGAUGACAUUGACAAGAUGAAAGAGCGAGCUGCCAUGAACAACUCCUUCAUCUACAUAAAGAUUCCACAGGUUCCACUGUGUGUCAGCUACAAGGGUGAGAAGAACAGUGUGGACUGGGGUGACCUUAACCUGGUGCUGCCCUGUCUGGAGUACCACAACAACACAUGGACAUGGCUAGACUUUGCCAUGGCUGUCAAAAGGGACAGCCGCAAAGCCCUGGUUGCCCAGGUAAUCAAAGAGAAGCUAAGGCUGAAGUCUGCAACAGGCUCUGAGGUCCGGGGAAAGCUAGAAACUAAAUCGGACCUGAACAUGCAACAGCAGGAAGAGGAGGAGAAAGCCCGGCUCCUCAUUGGUUUAAGUGUGGGCGACAAGAACCCUGGCAAGAAGUCCAUCUUUGGCAGGCGCAAAUGAUUUGGCGAUUCGAGUGGCUGCAGUACAGGAUCUGACUCUGGCUCAGGCUCCAGGGACUUGUGGGGUGGGAGGGGCUUCCCGUUAUCCACGAGGAUUUGUGGGUGUCAGAGCCCAUAGGCAUCACUCUUCAGCACCUGGUCUGUUCGCUGCAGGGCAUGGUGGACAGUAAUGCUGAGUUCUGUCUCACACUGAUCAGGCUCAGGGCCAGAGAGGCAACAAGAGAGCAAGACCCAGGGAAUGGGCCCAGGGCAGGACCCUAUUCCCUUGGGGUCAAGUGAAAGGGUAGGGGGAUAGUCCUGAUCAAGUGUGAUAAAUUUUUAUAGACAUAUAUAAAUAUAUAUAUAUUAUAUAUAUAUUUCUAAGUGUAACUGUCCUUCCUCUGUGCCAGGAAACGGGAGGGGGCUGAUCCUCUGAUCCUCACUCCACUGUCAUGUUUGAAAGAGGUAUUGGUGUUCUGGAGUGGGGGUCAACCCCUCCCCAGUCUCUGUGCUAAGUUCACUUGGGAGGAUGGCAGUAGGAGCCAGGGCUGGCCAUGGGUCCCCUACCCUUCCCCGUAGGAUAUACCCUGGAGAAUGGCAAAAUGAUUUAAAGAGAAAAAAAAAGAUAUUUUAAAUUUGAUGCUCA